GGAGCUGGGCUGGUGUGCGCGCGGCCGGAGUCUGUGGAGCUGGAAAUUCACCGGUCCAGGAAGACGUCUUUCCCGCGUCCCAGCACCGGUCCAGAAAGACGUCUUUCCCGCGUCCCAGCACCUCGGGCCACGCUCCUUCGUGAGAGCGCCCUCUCCAAGGAGGCCGGCCCUGGAUAUUUCACCCAAAAUAUUUAUUUUUUCUUUUUUUCUAGGCUCCUGUUUUCCUAAUAGCAUGAACAGCCCCCCCGUCAGCUCCUACCCCUUGGUCUCUGACCUGUUCCUCCUCCGAGGUGACCUCUAUCCUGAAUUUUGAAAACAUAUUAGUAUUGCCUGUUUCUGGACUUUGUGCAGAUGAAGUCAUUGGUAUGUAUUCAUUUGCAUCUAGUGUUUAUACAUUCAUAAAAUAGAUCACUGUGUAGCCAUUAAAAAUAAUGAGAGAGUGCUAUAUAAUUUCAUAUGAAACAUAUCAGGACACAUUGCUAAGUAAAAGCAAAGAGAAAGCAGACACCGAGUGUAGACUGUUAUAUGCAUGAAUGUCUCUGAACAGUAUAUGAGGCACCUUCAGGUCUCUUUUUUAUUUUUUUUUUUUUUGAGACAAUCUUUCUCUGUUGCCCAGGCUGGAGUGCAGUGGCGCAAUCUGGGCUCACUGCAACCUCCACCUGUCGGGUUCAGGCAAUUCUCCUGGCUCAGCCUCCCUAGUAGCUGGGAUCACAGGUUCCCGCCACCAUGCCCAGCUAAGUUUUUUUUUUUUUUUUUUUUGAGAUGGAGUCUCACUCUGUCACCCAGGCUGGAGUGCAGUGGUGCGGUCUCGGCUCACUGCAAGCUCCGCCUCCCGGGUUCAUGCCAUUCUCCUGCCUCAGCCUCCCGAGUAGCUGGGACUACAGGCGCCCACCACCACGCCUGGCUAAUUUUUUGUAUUUUUAGUAGAGAUGGGGUUUCACCGUGUUAGCCAGGAUGAUCUCGAUCUCCUGACCUUGUGAUCUGCCUGCCUCGGCCUCCCAAAAUGCUGGGAUUACAGGUGUGAGCCACCGUGCCUGGCCCCAAAGAUGAUUGUCUUAUAAAAGCCUAUGUAACCCUUUUCAUUUUUUCUUUAAAAAAUGUCUUCCUUUACCUCCUGGAACACAUCCAUACUUAUUCCCAUUGUAAUGCCCGUUCCUGAAUAAACAUCAUUGUUUUUUUAGAGAGGGAGAGAGAGUCCAUUGGUGAGAGAGUCUCACCAAUCUCCUGUCCCCAGGGCACUUCCACCCCUGGGUAUUUGUACUGAUCAACCAGGUUACGCUUUCAGCAUUUGCAAACUCAGGAUGGAGAUUUUAGACCCUCUUCAACCUCCAGGUUUCCUCUUUGCAAAGGCCAGCAGCAGAAGCAAAAGAGAUGGAGCCCGGGUUAGCAUUUAUUUUUCUAUUUACCAGUCAUUUGGAAUUUGGACAUUUUCUGUCCUGUGGUUGUGGUGAGGGUGUGGGUUUUGUGUUGUUUUAUAUAUUCUUUGUUAUUUUUUAUUCUAGUUUUUGUUUUUGUUUUGGAAGGUAUUUUAGAGAAAUAAGAUUUCUGUGGUUACCAUGACCUGCUGUUACAGAUUACAUGGUACCCUCUCUUCAUAUGUUGAAGUCCUAGCCACCCCGCCGAACCUCAGAAUGUGACUGUAUUUGGAGAUAGGGUCUUUACAGAGGAAAUCAAGUUAAAAUGAAGUCAUUAGGGCAGGCCCUAAUCCGAUAUGAUCCUGUGUUCUUAGAAGAGGAAAUGUGGACUCAGGUGUGUAUGGAGGGAAGAUGUCUUGCAAGCCCAAGGAGAAGAUGGCCAUCUGAGCCCACGUCCUGGAACAGAGACUUCCCUCACAGCCUCAGAAAGAACCAGCCCUGCUGACGUCUUGAUCUCAGACCUCCAGCCUCCAGAACUGGGAGACGAUUCAGUCAGCAUCUACACAACACAGGGUUGAACUGUGCGGGUCCACUUCUAUGCAGAUUAUUUUCUUUUUUCUUUUUUGAGACAGAGUCUCGCCCGGUUGCUCAGGCUGAAGUGUAGUGGUGUGAUCUUGGCUUACUGCAGCUUCCACCUCCCAGGUGCAAGUGAUUCUCCUGCCUCAGCUUCCCAAGUAGCUGGGACUAUGGGUACUCGCCACCACACCUGGCUAAUUUUUGUAUUUUUAGUAGAGAUGGGGUUUCACCAUGUUGGUCAGGCUGGUCUUGAACUCCUGACCCCAAGUGAUCUGCCUGCCUUGGCCUCCCAGAUUGCUGGGAUUACAGGUGUGAGCCACCGUGCCCGGCCCUAUAUAACUCUUUGUGCAAGUUUUUACCCCUAAAAGAUAUCUGCCAUCUCAGCCAUGGAACAGACACUGUAAGAACAUGAAGGCUCAAGGGCAGGGCUGGCUACAUAAUUUGUGGGACCCAUUACAAAAUGAACAUGGAGAAAAAACUAGAAAAAAGUGUAGUACAAGGUACUAUAAUAGAUUUUUCCUUUGAAAACAGUUUAAUACUUAUAAAAUGUAAUAGAGGGAAAUAGUGACACGUGAGUAACAAAAUGGGCGUAUCAAUUGGUCUAUGCUAUUUUUGGUGUUAUAAUUUUACCUAAUAUAAUAAGCAGCAACACUUUGUUAGUGAGACGGGCUUUCACCAUGUUGGCCAGGCUGGUCUGGAACUCCUGACCUCAGGUGAUCCGCCUGCCUCAGCCUUCCAAAGUGCUGGGAUUACAGGUGUGAGCCUCUGCGCCCGGCUGUGAUGUCUUGAUUGAUCAUAGGAUUUUUCUGGCUAUUCUAGCUACUUCCAAUUCGCUUCAGCCAAUUUAGUUGAAGUUUUAUCACUUGUGACUUCAGAGUCCUGGUUAAUAUCCUGUUGCCCUCAGGACAUGCAGGAUGGAGGAAGGCACCAGGGAGCCGAGGGAAGUGAGCAGAGAGGCAGUCACUUCAGGGCCACCAGCAUAGCCCCCGUCACUGUCCACAGACACAGGCCCUUCCCCUUCUCAUGGUUGAGCAGGCUCCACCUCACUUCCGUGUAUGACUUCAUAGACCGUUAGGUUCCGUGGUACCCUGGAGUCCACAGCUGCUGAAUCUGAAGGGCCAUCAGAAGACUGGCUUCUCCAUGAUGGUUUAUGGACUAAGGCAAAGAUGAGCAGAGCCAUGGCCCUCUUCUUUGUUCUCUGCUGGAUCCAAGAUGAAAUUGUGCUCCAAGUGUUUUCCAAGGUUCCGUAUGACCCAUCAUUUGAUGAAACAAGAACAGCAGUCAGAUCCAUUACAAAGAGAGACACACAAAAAAGCUAUUCCCAACAGAAGAGCUUGAACAAUGCUGCAUUUGCAUCAGGUUCAAAUGAGCGAGAGGAACAUUUGGCUAAAAUAUUUGAUGAAAUUCUACUGCAGGUGUUUCCAAAGUUUCCGUAUGACCCAUCAUUUAACGAAGCAACAGCAGUCAGAUCCAUUACAAAGACAGACAUGAGAAAAGGAACCAGCAUUGCUUGGAAUUCUCCUAAACCAGAAUAUUUCCUUGGCAGUGUGGACAAAAUUCCUGAUAAAGAUGAACACAUUUUAUCUUUUGUAGAUCACCUUUCAGAGGAGAAGAAUUUUAAAGAAUCCUGUCUGUUCGACAGGGAUUUAAGAGAGCAGUUAACUACUAUAGAUAAAGAAACACUUCAAGGAGCAGCUAAACCAGAUGCUCACUUUAGGACUAUGCCCUGCGGGCAGCUUCUGCACUUCCUGCAGAGGAACACCAUCAUCGCCGCCGUCUCAGGGGUGGCCAUCCUCAUGGCCAUCGUGCUGUUGCUGCUUGGGUUGGCCUCAUACAUCAGGAAGAAACAGCCAUCAUCUCCUCUGGCAAACACGACAUAUAAUAUUUUUAUAAUGGAUGGAAAGACAUGGUGGCACAAUUCUGAAGAAAAAAAUUUCACAAAACUUGCAAAAAAACAGAAACAGUUGAAGAGCAGCUCCUGUGUCUAAGCCAGGUCGUGGGGCCGUCAAACCAGGACUUGAAACCACAAUGCGAGGACAUUCUCCAUCUGCGCACCACAGGGAGGCAAUUCCAUUUCUGCCCGGGAGGUGUAUUCUACAAAAACGUCUGCUUCCCAUCCCAAUUUGAAUGGACCAAGAAAAACUGCUUUACCAUAGGACACUUGUGGCAAUAUGGCACCGAUGGCUGGCGUCGGUGAACCCGACAGACUAUGGAUUUAUCAUUUAAUAAAGCAUUGAUUCAUUUUUUCAGUCA